GGUUGCGGUUAGUGGACCGGGACCGGUAGGGGUGCUGUUGCCAUCAUGGCUGACCCCGACCCCCGGUACCCUCGCUCCUCGAUCGAGGACGACUUCAACUAUGGCAGCAGCGUGGCCUCCGCCACCGUGCACAUCCGAAUGGUUCUCCAGAGAGAUUGUACCUUCAGCAAACAAUAUAUGAGGAUACCUUCUGCACCCUCAGCCACACUGAAUAUCAUCAGAUUUUUUCAUCUCCGGCAAUCUGGUAGAUCAGGGAUGGUGAACAUUUUCUACAAAGGGCCAACCUUUCUGAGAAAAGUCUACAGCAUUCUUUCUCUGCAGGUUCUCUUAACUACAGUGACUUCAACAGUUUUUUUAUACUUUGAGUCUGUACGGACAUUUGUACAUGAGAGUCCUGCCUUAAUUUUGCUGUUUGCCCUCGGAUCUCUGGGUUUGAUUUUUGCGUUGAUUUUAAACAGACAUAAGUAUCCCCUUAACCUGUACCUACUUUUUGGAUUUACGCUGUUGGAAGCUCUGACUGUGGCAGUUGUUGUUACUUUCUAUGAUGUAUAUAUUAUUCUGCAAGCUUUCAUACUGACUACUACAGUAUUUUUUGGUUUGACUGUGUAUACUCUACAAUCUAAGAAGGAUUUCAGCAAAUUUGGAGCAGGGCUGUUUGCUCUUUUGUGGAUAUUGUGCCUGUCAGGAUUCUUGAAGUUUUUUUUUUAUAGUGAGAUAAUGGAGUUGGUCUUAGCCGCUGCAGGAGCCCUUCUUUUCUGUGGAUUCAUCAUCUAUGACACACACUCACUGAUGCAUAAACUGUCACCUGAAGAGUACGUAUUAGCUGCCAUCAGCCUCUACUUGGAUAUCAUCAAUCUAUUCCUGCACCUGUUACGGUUUCUGGAAGCAGUUAAUAAAAAGUAAUUAAAAGUAUCUCAGCUCAACUGAAGAACAACAAAAAAAAUUUAAUGAGAAAAAAGGAUUAAAGUAAUUGGAAGCAGUAUAUAGAAACUGUUUCAUUAAGUAAUAAAGUUUGAAACAAUGAUUAAAUACUGUUACAAUCUUUAUUUGUAUCAUAUGUAAUUUUGAGAGCUUUAAAAUCUUACUAUUCUUUAUGAUACCUCAUUUCUAAAUCCUUGAUUUAGGAUCUCAGUUAAGAGCUAUCAAAAUUCUAUUAAAAAUGCUUUUCUGGCUGGGCACAGUGGCUCACGCCUGUAAUCCCACCACUUUGGGAGACCGAGGCAGGUGGAUCACGAGGUCAAGAGGUUGAGACCAUCCUGGCCAACAUGGUGAAACCCCGUCUCUACUAAAAAUACAAAAAUUAGCUGGAUGUGGUGGCACACACCUGUAGUCCCAGCUAGUCAAGAGGCUGAGGCCAGAGAAUCGCUUGAACCUGGGAGGUGGAGGUUGCAUUGAGCCAAGAUCACGCCACUGCAUUCCAGCCUGGUGACAGAGCGAGACUCAGUCUCAAAAAAAAAAAAAAAAUUUUUCUUCCUAAAUUAGCCACGCAUAGCAGUUCGUUUGCAAUUCAAAAAUAAUUUUAUGAGUAGAUAAGAAUAUCAGUUUACCGUUGUCUAGUGAUUUUAUCUAAAUUUUCCCUGAAUUAUUAAGUAAUAUUGAUUUGGCUUUGAUUCUGAAGUAGUAGAGUCUUUACCAUUAUAAACUGUAAAUCUCUUUUUGCUUAAAAGGAAAAAAAUGUAAAAGAUAAAUUCCACAGAGAAUUAUUCAGUAUUACAUUAAAAUGUUAAUGACUUUUUAUUUUAAAUUGUACUAACAUUAAAAGUUGGCCUGAAAGUCAGAUAUUAUGACAAAAUUUGACAUUAAUUGUUUUUAAAGUAUAGAUUUCAUUUGAAAUUAUAGAAUGGUAAUGUGGUUAGAGGACACCAAAGAUACUGGGUCAUCAGCCAUUAAGUAUAUCUAUUUCAAAAUUAAAAUAUUUGGGAAGUAUUGUCUUAUGGUUUCAUUUGUGUUGGUCCACACAGCAUGUUAGGUCAGUGUACCAGUAACCAAUGAAAUUUUGUCAAAUUCCCUCACUGUACUAGUUUGUUAGGCUGCCAUAACAAAGUUCUACAGCUUGGGUGGCUUCAACAAGAAAUUUGUUUUCCCACAGUUCUGGAGGCUAAAAGUCCAAGAUCAAGGUGUUAGCAGGGUUGGUUUCCUUUGAGGCCUUUCUCUUUGAUUUGUAGAUGGCCAUCUUCUCCCUGUGUCUUUAAAUGGCCUUCCCUCUGUACUUGUCUGUGCCCAAAUUUCUUCUUCUUAUGAGGACACCAGUCAUACUGGAUUAGGGCCCACACUGAGGACCUCAUUUUUCCUUAAUUAUCUCUUUCAAAACCUAUCUCCAAAUACAGUCACAUUCUGAAGUGCUGGGAUUAGGAUUUCUUCAUGUGAAUUUUGGGGGGACUACAACUCAGCCCAUAACACCCCCUAAGUAUUUCCCAGCUAUUAAGUUGAAAUAAACUUGUAGUAUCAAUUUAAGCUUGCAUGAUUUGUAGAUGUAAAUUUGACUUUAUUAUCAUUAACUGUUGAAUUAUCAAGUGUAUGAUGCAGUGCAAUCAAGUUUAACAGCAUGGUGGGUAAGAGCAUCUAGAUUAGAAUCAUUGCAGUCCAACCAGGUGCUUAAGUGACAUUUGGCGAAUUAUUUAUCCUUCCUUAGGUCUUCUGCCUCAUCUUCAUAAUGGGAAUAAUGAUGUCUAGCUUAUUGGGCUGUUAUAAGGAUUAAAUGAGAUAGAUAAAUAAACUAAACUAAGUGCUUAAUUAAUGUCAGCUGAUGGUAUUAAUACCAUUUUCUUUUUUUUUUUUUUUUUUUUUUUUUAAUUUAUUUUUUUAUUGAUAAUUCUUGGUUGUUUCUCACAGAGGGGGAUUUGGCAGGGUCAUGGGACAAUAGUGGAGGGAAGGUCAGCAGAUAAACAAGUGAACAAAGGUCUCUGGUUUUCCUAGGCAGAGGACCCUGCAGCCUUCCGCAGUGUUUGUGUCCCUGAUUACUUGAGAUUAGGGAUUGGUGAUGACUCUUAACGAGCAUGCUGCCUUCAAGCAUCUGU